AGUGUUCCGGGAGCUGGGUUAUAAAAUGCCGGGUUAAGCGGCAACUCAGACUCAGGAUCCCGCUCACGACAUGGCCUCGGGCGCUCAGCUCCCGCCGCAGCCGUCGAGCUCAGAGGUCAGCGCCGUCCAGAGCCCAGGCGGGCGUCCCGGCGCCGGUCUGGAGGAAACAGCCCUGGGCGUUCCUCUCCCGCCGUCUCCGGGGGAGGCCCCUCUGCCCCGAAGCAACCGGAGCAGGUGCCCUGGGACCCGCCAGCCCGGAGCGGCCUCCCUCCACGCGGCGUCCGCAGCAGUCCCCGUGCGGCCCCGGCGCGGUACGGCGCCAGCCGGGAAAACCGCAGACGCGGUCCCCGCCGCCGCCCCAGAGCAAGCUCCGCGGCCGGCUCCACAGUCCCGCAAGCCGCGCAACCUGGAAGGCGACCUGGACGAGCGCCGGCUGCUCUGCCACUUGCAGCUGGCCCAGGACCGCGAGGCGCGCCUGUGGCGGGGCGGCAAACCCCAGGAUGAAAUCUGCGACGCCUUCGAGGAAGUCGUGCUGUGGCUCCUGCGGCUUCAGAACACCUUUUACUUCUCCCAGUCCACUUUUAACCUGGCCCUCACCAUCUUUGGCCGCCUCCUGAUUUCAGUGAAGGUAAAAGAGAAAUACCUGCAUUGCGCCACAAUUACUUCCUUGAGGCUCGCUGCAAAAGUUAAUGAAGAAGAGGAGUUUAUUCCACAAGUAAAAGACUUCACAAAGCACUAUGGCUCUGACUAUUCCCCGAAUGAGCUGCUGAGGAUGGAGCUGGCUAUUCUGGACAGACUGCACUGGGACCUCUAUAUUGGGACGCCGCUGGACUUCUUGACUAUAGUGAGUAAGGAGGUGUUUACAGAGUCUACCCUAAACUCGUUUGUGCCUUUGGAACAGCUGUUUACAACAUGGGAUGGCAAAGCACAGGCGUGCACACGCCCUUGCACAUGCACCACAGUGAGGUGACGCACAAGGCUCAUGACAUACGGAAGAGUGAAAAGGUAUCUUAAAUCCAACACAGUUCCACCAGACUCCCACUUCUAAAGGACAUUAAAUUAACUUUACAAAGAUUUUUAGACGGCACUAUUAUGGUGAGUUUCUCUUUUAAAUACACACUGCAAAAAUAUUUAACUUUCCAUUCUAUGAAUACUGUACAUAAAUAUCUGUCUGCUUUUGCUACACUUUACACACAUUCACUUAGCUGUCUUUAUUCACCUACACACAAUCCUUAUUGAAGCUUUAGACCAUAUUGAUCUGGCACUUAAAAAAAUAUCAUACAUUAGUUUGUAUUUGUUUUAGUUGGGGGAAUGAUGGUCAUCCUUAAGGAUAUGAUUCUGUUAGUAAGGCAAAAUUAUGCAAUGUGGAAAUCUCAUGGGGUUUUGGUUUGUUAUGAAGCAUGAAGAUUAAAUUACUAAAGACUGUUUCAUUACGAAAACUGGCCACCGUUGCCAAGUUGCAGAGUUUCGUCUUAUGAUAAGCAGAUACAAGUAACUUUUCUGCUACCUUGGUCUUGAAUAGUAUGUUUCUAUUUUUCAGAAUGGAAACAUUGUCAUCUAGGUACUUUCCGCUCAUAACGAUGAUGUCACAAAGCAGACUUUUUUUUUUUUUUGGUCCCGGAGUGGAAGCUCAGCUUGGCCACAGGAUGGGCAUUAAGCCUCAAGCCCCUUACGGAGCCAUGGAUAGGAAUGAAAAGGGUUGGGCAACAUUUGAUGUUCCCUGAUGGAAAUUUAAAUUGUUUGCACUUUUGAUCAUUGAUAUAGGAAAAGUAUGGCGUUUUCUGUUCUAACAUUAAAAACCAUGGUCUCCAGUUCCAUGCCCUGGUGGUCCUGAGCUGGCCCCAUGUGUUGGAGCUGCUGCCUCAGAGGAAUCCUUCCCUCCACGUCGCAUCCCUGACCAGGCAGCUGCAGCACUGUAUGGCGGGCCACCAGCUGCUGCAGUUCAAGGGCUCCACACUGGCCUUGGUCAUCAUCACCUUAGAGCUGGAGAGGCUCAUGCCCGGCUGGUGUGCUCCUAUAUCUGAUCUGCUAAAGAAAGCACAGGUAGACAUCAACUUUGCCCCAGACCAGGCUCUGUGUUUUGCCCCUUUAGCUGACACACUCUGACCCCAAAGGGGUACCCUUUGCCCUUGUAGCCUCUGGAAAAUGUUCUGGCCAUAACCCUGGAAAGAGUCUGCCCAAAGGCUAGGCUUUCCACACUUGGUCACGCUCUAUGCACUUGAGAUGGGACAUGUGUUCCCUUCACUGGACCAAUGGGGGUGGUCUCUGAGAGUGAGAGAAUCUUUAUCUCAAUGGGAGCCCUUGUAGCCAAGAGGACUGUGGGGAGUCAGGGGUAUGUCUGGCUUAGGAGGAAGCAACCCUGAGCUUAAUACUGAGGAGCAUAAAUUCUAAACUCCUUCACCUCUCCUUUGUAUGAGUGUGUGGUACCAGGUACAGGGGUACCAUGAGGCAAGCAUUGUGGGGGCACAAGGAGGAGAGGGGUGUGUCAGAAUCCCUCAGAACAGAUAGGUUAGGAUGGAAUGCAUAGUUAGACUAAUGACAACUUUACUGAGGUUGGAAAUGGAUGUCCCUGAGAUGGUAGGAUUAGUGGUCCUUAGUUGGGUGGUUGGACCUUCCUGAACUUGCUUCAUGCUAACAUUUUGGCACUCAAUUGCCAAUUUCUUAGAAUGUAUGAUGGUUCUGCUUGAAGAUGGCCACUCUAUUCUAAUACAGGUUGGUGAUAUGCAGUACAGCUGCUGCAAGGAACUUGUAAUGCAGCAACUGAGAAGUCUUCAGUCAUCCUCCUGCACAGACAACUUUGUGUCACCUGCCAACUAGCCCCUCUGCCUCCACCCCGGGGCUUUCAGAGCAUAGUGUGAAACCUCCUUGCUUGGACUACCAUGAGUUCUUUGGCUUGUUAUGAAUCCUGUAAAAAGGGAAGGUGGCUCUGGAAGAGCAACUGAGAAAAAGUUCCCAACUGAGCCCUUGGAAAAAAAAUAAAGGGGAGAGGGGAAAGGCAGGCUGAGGUCAGUAGAGGUCAGGGUGGUCUGAUAGACUAUGACCCUGUCUUCCCUUUUUCUCCUCUGGGCCUGAAGCCAGGGAGUAUGAAUGAAUGUUCAAAUGGCAGCUUGUUUUACCUUCCUUCUCCAGCAAGGGUUGGCAUUGGCCCCUGGGAGCGCUGGAAUAUGAAACCAAGAGGCAGGCCUGGCUCAGGGCUGAAGGGCUGGGGCUAGCUCUGACCAGUUCUUGCUGCUCUACCUGCCAGAGCUGGCCAGGUCCUUCCAACUUCCCAGGCUUAUCCCAAACACAUAUGUGGUGCUUCCAGUCCCAACUACCCUGCCUGCCACUCCUCACAUGGGACAGUCUCUGCAGAUGCAUUUACCCAACCAUGGCUAUGACUUAUGUCUUCCCUUUACAAGGACUGGAUUAUAAAGUAUGCUUUGUUUAAUGUAACUUGAGCAAGCUUUAGGCAUAUCUUUCCUUUGUUACUCUUAAGCAAAGUGGUUUCAGUUAUUAGUUUAACUAGAGGGAUUUUGUGCUAAUGAAUGGGUAUUAUAGGCUAACACCUGUGAUGGGAGGCACAGCUCUGAAUGCUUUCUGUUGGGAUGAGCAGGUUCUGAGGCCAAGCCUGCUCCAACCACAGUGCUGCCAGGAGGAGGAGCCGGCUGCCUCUCUCAUGCUGUGCUACCACAGAGCCAUUCUCUAAGCAGGGGAGUGCAGCUGACAAAGAUGCCAGCUGGGGCUGUGUAAGUUGUGUUGGGGGCAUGAAUGACUGAGCCACACAUUCAGAGGUGGUUUGUGAAGUCUUCCACUGUGAACUAUGGUUUUUUUUUUUUUUUUUUUUUUUUGGUGUGUUUGUGUAAAUGUGCUAAGCCAUGGGGUGGGAGGGGAAAGAUUUACUAGGUGCAAAGUGGUCAAGGGCCAGAUAUACUAUAAUUGUCUAUAUUAUAGAGUUAGUAUACAUCUGUAUUUUUUCUUGACACACUUUUGCUUGUUGGUGCUUUCGUUAAAAUUACACUUUAAUUGCUUCCGA